AACUCAAAUUGCAUAAACGGCAGAUCUCAGUCAUAAAAAUCUUUGUAUUAAAUAGGAUUCAAGUUACAUGCUCUGGUAACGUGGGUCUAAGAGGAUGCUAAUUGGUGACUUAUAUGUUCUAUCUACACUGGACCAUGGAAAAAAGCAAUAAUAGCACUUUGUUUAUUCUCUUGGGGUUUUCCCAAAAUAAGAACAUUGAAGUCCUCUGCUUUGUAUUAUUUUUGUUUUGCUACAUUGCUAUUUGGAUGGGAAACUUACUCAUAAUGAUUUCUAUCACGUGCACCCAGCUCAUUCACCAACCCAUGUAUUUCUUCCUCAAUUACCUCUCACUCUCCGACCUUUGCUACACAUCCACAGUGACCCCCAAAUUAAUGGUUGACUUACUGGCAGAAAGAAAGACCAUUUCCUAUAAUAACUGUAUGAUACAACUCUUUACCACCCAUUUUUUUGGAGGCAUAGAGAUCUUCAUUCUCACAGGGAUGGCCUAUGACCGCUAUGUGGCCAUUUGCAAGCCCCUGCACUACACCAUUAUUAUGAGCAGGCAAAAGUGUAACACAAUCAUCAUAGUUUGUUGUACUGGGGGAUUUAUACAUUCUGCCAGUCAGUUUCUUCUCACCAUCUUUGUACCAUUUUGUGGCCCAAAUGAGAUAGAUCACUACUUCUGUGAUGUGUAUCCUUUGCUGAAAUUGGCCUGUUCUAAUAUACACAUGAUAGGUCUCUUAGUCAUUGCUAAUUCAGGCUUAAUUGCUUUGGUGACAUUUGUUGUCUUGUUGUUGUCUUAUGUUUUUAUAUUGUAUACCAUCAGAGCAUACUCUGCAGAGAGACGCAGCAAAGCUCUUGCCACUUGUAGUUCUCAUGUAAUUGUUGUGGUCCUGUUUUUUGCACCUGCAUUGUUCAUUUACAUUAGACCGGUCACAACAUUCUCAGAAGAUAAAGUGUUUGCCCUUUUUUAUACCAUCAUUGCUCCCAUGUUCAACCCUCUCAUAUACACGCUGAGAAACACAGAGAUGAAGAACGCCAUGAGGAAAGUGUGGUGUUGUCAAAUACUCCUGAAAAGAAAUCAACUUUUCUGAAUUGUUUCUGCUUUUCAUGCCGUGGUUCCCUGAUGAAUGAGAAAAAUUCACUCUCAUCUUGCUCUUGUCCUUAAUGUUUGGAGAGAAAAGUGGGCAAACAGGAAGCAUAUCCCUUCUGUGGUUUUAUACUUCUACAUUGACAUCUCUUUAACAAAUUGAACAUUAUUCUUAUCCAUACUCUCCUCCGCCUUUCUUAAUCAUUACGAUUGUGCUUAUGUGACAUGAAAUAACCAGAAAAUUUCUUAAAAAUAAAGGAUUACAUGGCGUUGUGUUGAAAAAAUAAAACAGAUUAUGUGUUUUUUGUGCCUUAAAGUUCUGAGAAGAUCAAUGAAAUAUUACUCUCAGCUUUUACAUUUUUACUCAAGUCUAAACACAGAAAAUGCAUGUAUUGCCUGUGUACAGCUCACGAAUUUUUGCAAACUGAGCAUGAUUGUGAAAUCAGCAACUGAAUUAAGAGACAGAAAUUAUCAGCACAUCAGAGGUCCUCCUUAUUCCUCUUUAUGAUUAAUACCUCCCAAAGUUAACCACAAUAUUUAUUCCUAAAAUAAAUAGUUUUCGGCUGGGCACGGUGCCUCAUGCCUGUAAUACCAGCACUCUGGGAGGCUGAGGUGGGUGGAUCAUGAGGUCAGGAAUUCGAGACCAGCCUGGCCAAGAUGGUGAAACCCCGUCACUACUAAAAAUACAAAAAUUAGCUGGGCGCAGGGGCGAGCACCUGUAAUCCCAGCUACUCGAGAGGCUGAGGCAGGAGAAUCGCUUGAACUCGGGAAGCGGAGGUUGCAGUGAGCCGAGAUCAUGCCACGGCACUCUAGCCUGGGUGACAGAACAAGAUUCCGUCUGAAAUAAUAAUAAUAAUAAUGAUAAUAAUAAUAAUAAUAAUAAUGUUUUUAUCUUUUCUUGUACUUUGAAGAGUAAGAGUGAUUUACAUUUUGUUGCUGCGUGUGUGUCUUCUUAGUGUUUCAUUUGUGAGUCAUUUCUCAUGUUGGUAAGUUUUCUGACUGUUUUCAUUGAUGUAU